AGGGAAGCUUGGUUAAAAACAGUUAUGGCAGUGGGAGUCGAAGCGAGGGUCUGAAGUUCACGACUACUAGAAGGGGAGGGGAGUGGAAAGGCUCUCAGUGAAAAAGGUAUUAGAAUUAUUUCUGAAUUAUCAGUCUCUCAUUUGUGCUUUGGAGAAGCAGAAAAGGCAAAAGGGGUCUUUGGCCAUCUUCUGCUGGAGCUUCCAGGGAGGAUGUGUCUCCAAGAGACCAGAUGUACCGAGUUUGAAAUCCCAGAAGCCCAAGAGGAAAAGAAUCACAGGGAGGAAAAGACUGUCCAAAGGCUUCUGGAGUCUUCUGUUCUCUAACCUUGGAAGGUUUUGAACAAUAUUUCUCAGAGGAUAGCCUUUCACUUAUUCAUCUGUCCAGCAUGACUCAUCCCCGGGAGUGUUGAAUGUCUCCUGUCUUCCUCCAGCAUUCACAAACCAGGAACGGCUAGCUUUUUGACCUGUUGCAUGAUGGAAUUUGAACAUUACUUCAAGAGGUUUUGUAUUUUGGAUUAGUUAAUUGGGUUUGUCCUCUGCUGACUGUUUCUUCGGAUGCAUUUUUUGGUGUGCUCUUGAGGGAUUAAAUGCAAAGAGAUCACACCAUGGACUACAAGGAAAGCUGCCCAAGUGUAAGCAUUCCCAGCUCCGAUGAACACAGAGAGAAAAAGAAGAGGUUUACUGUUUAUAAAGUUCUGGUUUCAGUGGGAAGAAGUGAAUGGUUUGUCUUCAGGAGAUAUGCAGAGUUUGAUAAACUUUAUAACACUUUAAAAAAACAGUUUCCUGCUAUGGCCCUGAAGAUUCCUGCCAAGAGAAUAUUUGGUGAUAAUUUUGAUCCAGAUUUUAUUAAACAAAGACGAGCAGGACUAAACGAAUUCAUUCAGAACCUAGUUAGGUAUCCAGAACUUUAUAACCAUCCAGAUGUCAGAGCAUUCCUUCAAAUGGACAGUCCAAAACACCAGUCAGAUCCAUCUGAAGAUGAGGAUGAAAGAAGUUCUCAGAAGCUACACUCUACCUCACAGAACAUCAACCUGGGACCGUCUGGAAAUCCUCAUGCCAAACCAACUGACUUUGAUUUCUUAAAAGUUAUUGGAAAAGGCAGCUUUGGCAAGGUUCUUCUUGCAAAACGGAAACUGGAUGGAAAAUUUUAUGCUGUCAAAGUGUUACAGAAAAAAAUAGUUCUCAACAGAAAAGAGCAAAAACAUAUUAUGGCUGAACGUAAUGUGCUCUUGAAAAAUGUGAAACAUCCGUUUUUGGUUGGAUUGCAUUAUUCCUUCCAAACAACUGAAAAGCUUUAUUUUGUUCUGGAUUUUGUUAAUGGAGGGGAGCUUUUUUUCCACUUACAAAGAGAACGGUCCUUUCCUGAGCACAGAGCUAGGUUUUACGCUGCUGAAAUUGCUAGUGCAUUGGGUUACUUACAUUCCAUCAAAAUAGUAUACAGAGACUUGAAACCAGAAAAUAUUCUUUUGGAUUCAGUAGGACAUGUUGUCUUAACAGAUUUUGGGCUUUGUAAAGAAGGAAUUGCUAUUUCUGACACCACUACCACAUUUUGUGGGACACCAGAGUAUCUUGCACCUGAAGUAAUUAGAAAACAGCCCUAUGACAAUACUGUAGAUUGGUGGUGCCUUGGGGCUGUUCUGUAUGAAAUGCUGUAUGGAUUGCCUCCUUUUUAUUGCCGAGAUGUUGCUGAAAUGUAUGACAAUAUCCUUCACAAACCCCUAAGUUUGAGGCCAGGAGUGAGUCUUACAGCCUGGUCCAUUCUGGAAGAACUCCUAGAAAAAGACAGGCAAAAUCGACUUGGUGCCAAGGAAGACUUUCUUGAAAUUCAGAAUCAUCCUUUUUUUGAAUCACUCAGCUGGGCUGACCUUGUACAAAAGAAGAUUCCACCACCAUUUAAUCCUAAUGUGGCUGGACCAGAUGAUAUCAGAAACUUUGACACAGCAUUUACAGAAGAAACAGUUCCAUAUUCUGUGUGUGUAUCUUCUGACUAUUCUAUAGUGAAUGCCAGUGUAUUGGAGGCAGAUGAUGCAUUCGUUGGUUUCUCUUAUGCACCUCCUUCAGAAGACUUAUUUUUGUGAGCAGUUUGCCAUUCAGAAACCAUUGAGCAAAAUAAGUCUAUAGAUGGGACUGAAACUUCUAUUUGUGUGAAUAUAUUCAAAUAUGUAUAACUAGUGCCUCAUUUUUAUAUGUAAUGAUGAAAACUAUGAAAAAAUGUAUUUUCUUCUAUGUGCAAGAAAAAUAGGGCAUUUCAAAGAGCUGUUUUGAUUAAAAUUUAUAUUCUUGUUUAAUAAGCUUAUUUUUAAACAAUUUAAAAGCUAUUAUUCUUAGCAUUAACCUAUUUUUAAAGAAACCUUUUUUGCUAUUGACUGUUUUUUCCCUCUAAGUUUACACUAACAUCUACCCAAGAUAGACUGUUUUUUAACAGUCAAUUUCAGUUCAGCUAACAUAUAUUAAUACCUUUGUAACUCUUUGCUAUGGCUUUUGUUAUCACACCAAAACUAUGCAAUUGGUACAUGGUUGUUUAAGAAGAAACCGUAUUUUUCCAUGAUAAAUCACUGUUUGAAAUAUUUGGUUCAUGGUAUGAUCGAAAUGUAAAAGCAUAAUUAACACAUUGGCUGCUAGUUAACAAUUGGAAUAACUUUAUUCUGCAGAUCAUUUAAGAAGUAACAGGCCGGGCGCGGUGGCUCACGCCUGUAAUCCCAGCACUUUGGGAGGCUGAGGCGGGCAGAUCACCUGAGGUCAGGAGUUGGAGACCAGCCUGACCAACAUGGACAAACCCCGUCUCUACUAAAAAUACAAAAUUGGCAGGGUGUGGUGGCACAUGCCUAUAAUCCCAGCUACUUGGGAGGCUAAGGCAGGAGAAUCGCUUGAACCCGGGAGGCGGAGGUUGCAGUGAGCCGAGAUCGCACCAUUGCACUCCUGCCUGGGCAACAAGAGUGAAACUCCAUCUCCAAAAAAAAAAAGAAAAAGUAACAAAAGGAAAUUAUUUGUUUUUGAAAUACCAGUUCAACUUUGUGGAUUAUUUUUCCUCUGAAGGAAAAGAAAAGGCUUAAUGGUUAGGAUUUUUAAGUAUUCCCAAAGAUCUGAAGGGUAAUAAAAUGUACUGGAUUUUUUAAGGUGGUACCAAAAAUGAAUGUCUGUCAUAUAUUUAUAUUACAAAUACAUUAUAUUUAUGUUCUAUUCAUCUUUUGAAUGUUUAGUAUGCUAUUAAGUCAUUCUGAAUCUUUGUAUUUGCUUUUGCAAAUAGGUAUUUCAAAGCUCUUUUCCUAACUGGUUAAGUAAAAUAAAAAAUUGAGCUUUCUAGAAUAUUUGCCUAAUUGGGAAUUAAAAAGUAAAAUAAUAGGCCAGGCAUGGUGGCUCAUGCCUAUAAGCACCCUGGGAGGCCGAGGCAGGCAGAUUAUUUGAGCUCAGGAGUUUGAGACCAUCCUGGGCAACAUGGCGAAACCCUAUCUCUACAAAAAAUACAAAAAUUAGCCAGACAUGGUGGCACAUGCCUUUAGUCCCAGCUACUCUGGAGGCUGAAGUUGGAGGAUGGCUUGAGCCCACGAGAUGGAAGUUGCAGUGAACUGAAAUUGUGCCACUGCACUUUUCAGCCUGGGUGCCACAGCGAGACCCUAGUUAAGAGAAAAAAAAAGUAAAAACAAAUUGUGGGUCAAAGUAAAUGUAUACAGUUUUAUUACAAUGUAACAAAAGUUGAAAAUCAGGCAGAUGUGUAUUCAGUAUCCAAUUCAAUAUAUCUUAGAAAAAGCACAGGAAACAGACCUUAAAAUUGUAACCUACCAACUAACUUACAUGCUUAUAAAAGUAAAGGAGAAUAACUGGCCGGGCACGGUGGCUCAUGCCUAUAAAAUUCCAGCACUUUGGGAGGCCAAGGCAGGAGGAUCACUUGAGCCUAUGAGUUCAAGACCAGCCUAGGCAAUGUAGUGACACCUCAUUUCUAUUUAUUUUAAAAAAAAGAGAGAGUAACUACAGAAGAACUUUAAAAAAUAAAAAAUAAGCUUACCUUGGAUUCUUGGCUUAGAGUAGAGGUUUUUUUUAAGUUAUGGAGGAAACAUUUUUGUAAAAGUUUAAUGACCCACUUUAGAUGCUCCAAGAACAAGCAUCCCUUCCAUGUAUGUCUUGAGAAAGAAAUCACAGAAGCAUUUCUCACCAAUACUCUUUGGCUUAAAAUGUUCAGCAGAAUUGGGCAGUGGGGGUGACUUUUCUUAUAUUAAUAAUAUUUACAUCCAAUACACUGAAUCUUCCUUUAGAGGUAAGACUUUAAUAUCUAUACUGUAAAUAUUUGGUUUAUUUGGCACUACUGUAAGUUUUGUUUUUCACAAAGCUCUUAUUAUGAAGCAAAAUAAAAAUUCUAGUUUCUUGUAUGAUUUUUUGUACUCAUUCAUUCCUGUUAAGCUGCCAAAAAUUAAAGUGCAAUAUUGUAUAUUUUUAAGAACAAAUUUAAAAUAGAAUUUUGAUGUUUCUCAGAUCACAAGAAAUACAAAUCUAUAUAGUAUAAUAAAAUCAGCAAAAAGAUCAA